GUUCGCGCGACGACCGCGGGGUCGGCGGGCGGGGCGAGGCCCUGGACGGCGGCGGCAGUGGGGCUCCUCCUUCUGUUUCCCAGACCGAGAGCCGCGCCGGCACCAUGUCAGCUUACCCUAAAAGCUACAAUCCGUUCGACGACGACGGGGAGGACGAAGGCGCCCGGCCGGCCCCUUGGAGGGACGCCCGAGACCUCCCCGACGGGCCCGACGCGCCCGCGGACAGGCAGCAGUACUUGCGGCAGGAGGUCCUCCGCAGGGCUGAGGCCACGGCCGCCAGCACCAGCAGGUCCCUGGCCCUCAUGUACGAGUCCGAGAAGGUUGGGGUCGCCUCUUCCGAGGAGCUCGCCCGUCAGCGAGGAGUCCUGGAGCGCACAGAGAAGAUGGUGGACAAGAUGGACCAAGAUUUGAAGAUCAGCCAGAAACACAUCAAUAGCAUUAAGAGCGUGUUUGGGGGGCUGGUCAAUUACUUCAAAUCCAAACCAGUAGAGACCCCACCUGAACAGAAUGGCACCCUCACCUCCCAGCCCAACAACAGAUUGAAAGAAGCUAUAAGUACAAGUAAAGAACAGGAAGCAAAGUACCAGGCCAGCCACCCAAACCUUAGAAAGCUGGAUGAUACAGACCCUGUCCCCAGAGGGGCUGGUUCUGCCAUGAGUACUGAUGCUUACCCAAAGAACCCACACCUUCGAGCCUAUCACCAGAAGAUCGACAGCAACCUAGAUGAGCUGUCCAUGGGACUGGGUCGUCUGAAGGACAUAGCCCUGGGGAUGCAGACAGAAAUUGAGGAGCAAGAUGACAUUCUUGACCGGCUGACAACCAAAGUGGACAAGUUAGAUGUCAACAUAAAAAGCACAGAAAGAAAAGUUCGACAACUCUGAAGACAGACGGAUUUCCACUCUAUUGUGAUGAAAAGAUUUGAAAGAUCUUUUUUUGAACUUCCAAGAAAUUUCAUUUACUAUUUUAGUAUGUAAAUUAAUGUGUGUUUGCAAAUGUUAUAAUAGAGUAGGUCUUAAGACAUUUUUGCUGUUAUAAGGAAGUGUUUGUCCCACAUUUUCCUAGGGUUAACACCUCACCAAGUUCUUCCAGCAAAAUGCUUAUUAGAGUUUUUGUCUGAGCACAGUAGCCUGGCCCUGCAUAUCUUGGGCGUUUGAUUACCAUGCUGGAAUAAGAAGAGUUGCAUUUCUCAUUUUAAUGAGCAUAUGGAAAGAUGGGAACAGAAUUUCAGUCUUGCAGCCAUGAGCCUCUAUUUCUCAUUCCUAAGCCUUACCAUGAGUCAGAGUGUUAAGGGGGCCUGUGAACCAGUCGUUUGGUGGAGGAGGGUCCUUCCCACACCUUUGUUUAGGAGUCAUCAUUCACACACACACACACACACACACACACACACACACACACACACACUCUCUGAGCACAUUAUCUGUGAUUCUUUCAUCCUCCCAGAAAGGAUCAGUGUUAGAAUGGGAAAUAGAGUGUGCCAUCUUGCUCUUUUGUUGGCAGAUGUCCCCGCUUCCCUCCAGCCCCCCAUCCUUGGCAUGUAUAUUAGUAGGAGGGCUUCACACCAGCACUGCUCACUGCGACUCCUGGAAAUGUGUGGGGAAUUGGGUGAGCCCCUCUUCCCCACGUGCUCCCAUCUGUAACUCUCCAUCUGUGAUUUGCAACAGGUCUUCCACUGGCUCGAGGCUGCGAGGCUGACCGACAGGGGCGCCCAAUAGAGUUUGUGGGAAUGGAGUAUUGCACAGAUGCAGCUGCACAAUGGUCUUCCUCCACCCCUCUGGGAAUCACCAUUAGGCAGGCCUCAGUAGGGCAAAAUGUUUAUUUGGUACCGGGGGUCUCCUGACCUGUCUAGCAUUCCCACCCACUCUUCUGCACUUCUUGCAAGGUAACUUGAAUCAUCACUUAUUUCUCUGCCACCUGGUUUUAGGACUGGCACUCUAUAAAUGACGCUGACUUUGUAUAGAAGGAUUUUGCUAAGGGGGCAAAAAGCCCAGAUACCAUUUUAACUGGCCCAGUUCAUUUUCUCCUUUCAUUUUACAAAAGAAAUCAUGCAGAAGCAUCAAUUAAAACUGAUUUAUUUAUGUUGGUACAUCCAACAAAAUAGUUGGAGCCACAAGGCCCUUGUCUUUUUAAAAAAACAAAAUAUUUUGAAGAUGGUGAAAGUGACUGAUUUUAAUAAUGAGAUAGGUCACUUAAAAUAACAGUGCCUUUGACCUUAAAACAUGGCACUGGCCCAUGUGACCUUUGCCAUUUCCCAGUACUUCCCUUUACAGUCUGCAGCCUAUAAACAGUGGUGUCUCAAAGCAAAGGAAACCUCCACAAGUGCUGCAACAGUGCAUUAGUUUUUAUGUAGCAAUUUGUUUAUAAAAAUUCCCAUCCCAUAAUGCAUGACCUUCCUAAAAAUAUCCACAGCCUCCAUAGGCAAGGUGAGCUUUCUGUGCUACCCACUUGUUAGAUUCCAGCCACCUCAGGGAUUCUGAUCCAUGUCAUUAACGACCAUCCCAGGGUGUGAGGGCCUGAUUAAAGCUUAUCGAACUAGACAUUUGUUUAUUAGAUGAGCUCGGCAUUAUUAUUUUCUCAAUAACUGGUAGAAGGGAAAUUUUAAACAUAACACUCAACCCAAACAAAACUACUUCGUGAGGCUUUCAGCAAAAAGGCUGCUUAAAAGCAUGAACCCGGGAUGCAGAGCAGCUUUUGUGCACGGUUCCACUUACUGUAAUUGUUUCUGGUUCUUUCCUCUAACACCUUCCAUGUAUGUCAACUUUUUAUCACCGUCAGGCAUAGACUCGUGGAGAUUAGUCAUUAUAGCUCAGACCUAAGCUAAUUAUUUAAAAUAAAUACAUGUAAAGGCCACUGCCACAUUCUCAGCAGACUUCCACUUGCCUAAUGAGAUUAGUGAUUCAACUGACUUGAAGCACAGUAACAUCUUAUUUUAUGCACAUUCCCUGUCUUUUGCUGGACUGAUGAAGCCAGUCACCCGCCCUUCUCUGUUUUUUGGUUUUUUUUUUCUUAACCCCAGGUAUAUGGAAGGGGAGUUGCCUUCACUUUUCUGGAAAUUUGUCUUCGUCUGACAUAUUAGAGGGCCUCGUUUUGUCCUGUUCUUGUUCAGACCCUCUCGUUCUACGUCCUGUGCUGAGGGGACUGUCCGUAAGCUACAGGACAGCGAGCUGGUCCUUUCUGCCACUUCUUCCCCACUCCCAUGCCCAGGAAGGCCUGGUUGCUGAUGCUACUUUAUAAAUGAGUUGCUUGCAUUUUCACAGAGAAUGAAGGAAGACGUAACAUGGCUCCAGAAACUUUUCACAUGAUGAUUGGGAUCGACAAAAAAAUGCUACCCUCUAGACUAGACACAUUUCAUGGAGACAAGCAAAAUGGUGCCAGGGCUGGGCUGACUGUGGGAUGGGAUUUGGUACUGCAGACAGAUUUUGAUUUCCACAGUUGAGCUGGAAACAAACUGUGCCUUCAAAAAAUGACUUUUCUAACUUAAGGUUGGUUAUAUGUUAAGUGUGCUACUAACUUAAAAAAUAGUGGCUGGGCGCGGUGGCUCAUGCCUGUAAUCCCAGUGCUUUGGGAGGCCAAGGCGGGGGGAUCACGAGGUCAGGAGAUCGAGACCAUCCUGGCUAACACGGUGAAACCCCAUCUCUACUAAAAACACACAAAAAAUUAGCUGGGCGUGGUGGUGGGCGCCUGUAGUCCCAGCUACUCAGGAGGCUGAGGCAGGAGAAUGGCAUGAACCUGGGAGGCAGAGCUUGCAGUGAGCCGAGACAGCGCCAUUGCACUCCAGCCUGGGCAACAGAGCAAGACUCCGUCUCAAAAAAAAAAAAAAAAAAAAAAUAGUGCACUCUCUGGCUGGUCACGGUGGCUCACGCCUGUAAUCUCAGCACUUUGGAAGGCCAAGGCAGGCGGAUCACGAGGUCAGAAGAUCGAGACCAUCCUGGCUAACACAGUGAAACCCCGUCUCUACUAAAAAUAUAAAAAAUUAGUCGGGCAUGGUGGCGGGCGCCUGUAGUCCCAACUACUCGGGAGACUGAGGCAGAAGAAUGGCGUGAACUCAGGAGGCGGAGCUUGCAGUGAGCCAAGGCGACAGAGCAAGACUCUGUCUCAAAAAAUAAAAAAUAGUGCACUGUCCUUCGAGAAAGUUUUCUAACAUCUAGUAAUUUGUAACUUAGAAGUGGAGUUGCCUUGUGGAUGUCUUUUUUGCAUUCUGUAGGAAAUGAAACGUGAAUUUAACUCGGGUUGCAAGAAAUAAAAAUGUCAGUGCAUUUAAA